GCACUUCCGGCAGCGCCGGGGAGCAGUCCGCUACGGAGGUGAGUGCAGGGCUCCGGGCGCUGUGUGCCGUGCCCUGUCCCCCAGGCUCUGGGUCCGGUUGAGACGCACUCCCACCCUGGGUGCUGCAGGGUCUCCCGUGGCCUACGCUGCCAGGAGGCCCAGGCUGGGAGAGGGAGCAGGGCGGCGGCCCGGGGUGCUCUUCCGCGCUCCUCGACUCCAGCUUUGGUCUUUGUGGCUCAAUAGCUUGCGCCCAUUGGAAGGGGAAACGCACGUUGCUGUCCCAGCCACGAGGCCCUGAGCAUUUAGCACUUGGUCGACGGGGGAAGAUGUGUCGGUGCAGCUAAAAGAUGGAAUAUUUGCGGGCGUGAAGCGGCCCGAGGUGAUACCACAAGUCUUUUGACAUGCUGAGGUCUGGCAGGAACAUUAACCUAUGUGCAUCCCGAGUAUGGACCGUGUGCUCCCAGGCUCCUGACAUAGGGUCAUGAAUUAGGGCCGAGUGGGAGCGCAGAGCCCCUCCCAGUCACCCGGCAGCAGAAGCAGCCCGGCUUUUGGAGGACAUUGUCUCCUGGAGCAGUGUCAGUCCCAAAAGCCUCCAACCCCUAGAGCUCCAGCCCUUCUCUGAGACGGGGACCAGGGGAUGGCAGCCAUGCACCUGACAGCCUGGCCCCAGGGACUUCACGGAUCCCCUGAAGCUCAUCCAUGGACUUCCAUGGACUACAGGGCCUGAGCUAUGGAAUUGGCCCUAGGGCAGCAGGAACCUAUUGUUUCAGAAGUCGGUGACCUUUGAGGACGUGGCUGUGUACUUCACCCAGGCGGAAUGGGAUGGCCUGUCCCCUGCACAGAGGACCCUGUACAGGGAUGUGAUGCUGGAGAAUUAUGGGAAUGUGGCCUCCCUGGGAUUUCCACUUCUCAAACCUGCUGUGAUCUCACAACUGGAGGGAGGAAGUGAGCUGGGGGGCUCAUCUCCACUGGCUGCAGGAACAGGCCUCCAGGGCCUCCAGACUGAUGGAGUCUCGCUCUGUCGCCCAAACUGGAGUGCAGUGGCAAGAACUUGGCUCACCGCAACUUCCGUUUCCCGGGUUCGAGCAAUUCUCCUGCCUCAUCCUCCCGAGUAGCUGGAACUACAGUAGAUAUUCAGACUGACAAUGAUUUGACAAAGGAAAUGUAUGAAGGAAAAGAGAAUGUAUCAUUUGAACUUCAAAGAGACUUUUCCCAGGAAACAGACUUUUCAGAAGCCUCUCUUCUAGAGAAACAACAGGAAGUCCACUCAGCAGGAAAUAUAAAGAAGGAGAAGAGCAACACCAUUGAUGGAACAGUGAAAGAUGAGACAAGCCCCGUGGAGGAGUGUUUUUUUAGUCAAAGUUCAAACUCAUAUCAGUGUCAUACCAUCACUGGAGAGCAGCCCUCUGGGUGUACAGGAUUGGGGAAAUCCAUCAGCUUUGAUACAAAACUCGUGAAGCAUGAAAUAAUUAAUUCUGAGGAAAGACCUUUCAAAUGUGAAGAAUUAGUAGAGCCCUUUAGGUGUGACUCUCAACUUAUUCAACAUCAAGAGAACAACACUGAGGAAAAGCCUUAUCAGUGUUCGGAGUGUGGCAAAGCUUUCAGCAUUAAUGAGAAAUUAAUUUGGCAUCAGAGACUUCACAGUGGGGAGAAACCCUUCAAAUGUGUGGAGUGUGGGAAAAGCUUCAGCUACAGUUCCCAUUAUAUCACACAUCAGACAAUCCACAGUGGGGAGAAGCCCUAUCAGUGUAAGAUGUGUGGGAAGGCCUUCAGUGUUAAUGGAAGCCUAAGUAGGCAUCAGAGAAUCCAUACGGGAGAGAAGCCCUAUCAGUGCAAGGAAUGUGGAAAUGGCUUCAGCUGUAGUUCUGCAUAUAUUACACAUCAGAGAGUCCACACUGGAGAGAAACCUUACGAGUGUAAUGACUGUGGGAAAGCGUUCAAUGUUAAUGCAAAAUUAAUUCAACAUCAGAGAAUCCAUACUGGAGAGAAACCUUAUGAAUGUAAUGAAUGUGGAAAAGGCUUCAGGUGCAGCUCCCAGCUUAGGCAGCAUCAGAGCAUCCACACAGGAGAAAAGCCCUAUCAGUGUAAAGAGUGUGGAAAAGGCUUCAAUAAUAAUACAAAACUCAUUCAGCAUCAGAGAAUCCACACAGGUGAGAAACCCUAUGAAUGCACUGAAUGUGGAAAAGCCUUCAGUGUCAAAGGGAAGUUAAUCCAACACCAGAGAAUUCACACAGGCGAGAAACCCUAUGAGUGUAAUGAAUGCGGGAAAGCCUUCAGAUGUAACUCCCAAUUUCGGCAGCAUCUGAGAAUUCACACUGGGGAGAAGCCCUAUGAGUGUAAUGAGUGUGGAAAGGCCUUCAGCGUUAAUGGGAAACUAAUGCGGCAUCAGAGAAUUCACACUGGGGAGAAACCUUUUGAAUGUAAUGAGUGUGGGAGAUGCUUUACUUCUAAAAGAAACCUACUUGAUCAUCACCGAAUCCAUACUGGAGAAAAGCCCUAUCAAUGUAAGGAAUGUGGGAAAGCCUUCAGUAUCAAUGCCAAACUAACUAGGCAUCAGAGGAUACAUACUGGGGAGAAACCUUUCAAAUGUAUGGAAUGUGAGAAAGCAUUCAGCUGUAGUUCUAACUAUAUUGUGCACCAGAGAAUCCAUACAGGAGAGAAACCCUUUCAGUGUAAGGAGUGUGGAAAAGCCUUCCAUGUUAAUGCCCAUUUAAUUCGGCAUCAGAGAAGCCACACUGGGGAGAAACCCUUCAGAUGUGUGGAAUGUGGCAAAGGCUUCAGCUUUAGUUCUGACUACAUUAUACAUCAGACAGUCCACACUUGGAAGAAACCCUAUAUGUGUAGUGUGUGUGGGAAAGCAUUCAGGUUUAGCUUCCAGCUCAGUCAGCAUCAGAGUGUCCAUAGUGAAGGAAAAUCCUAAUAAUGAGAAAGAUAUAGAAAACUCUUAAGGUUAAUGCCAAAAUGGAUCAAGUAUCAUCAGAUUCAUCCAUUGAAAAACCUCCAAGAGGGCAUGAAUAUGGCAGAGUCUUCAUAUGGAAACAGUUUUUAUUCUAUUCAGUUUAAAUCAGGAAAGGAUGACCAGUUAAAGAGAAACAUCCAAAAAUAGCUUUGUUUUGUACCAACAGGAAUUAGAAAAUAUAAUGAAAAGAUUUCGUUCCCAGCAGCAUCAAGAAAAGUAGAUUUUCUAGAAAUAAACAGUUAUGGAGGACUUGUAUGGAGAAAUUUAAGUCUUCACUGAGGGCCACUUUACAAAGGAAAUUUGAAUAAAUGGAGAGAGAGAGAAGCCUUGUUGUUGGAUAGGAAAACCCGUACUAAAGAUACUCUACCUACAUUAAUUUAUUUGUUUAAUUUUUGACAACAAGCAUGUAUUACUUUUGAAAAGAUGAAAAAUAAAGAUUUAUUUAAAAAAGGAAAAA